AUUUCUCAUACUUUGACUUCUAACAGUGAGCAGUUGAACUUGAGUCAGUUACAGGAGGAGGAAAUUGACUGCAAAGAAAUACGAGAAAACUUUGGCUGCGUCUUGCUCCUGUACACGGAUGACCUUCUGCUGGAACAUGCCAUGGCAGUUGGGUGUGCGAAGGGGACGGAUGCCCUGCUUCAGCACCUGGAGAACUGUGUGUAUAAGGUGUCCAAGAAGAAAGCUCAGAUCUGCAGACAGCAGGUACACUACCUGGGAUUCGCUAUUCGGAAAGGGGAGCGCAGCCUGGGGUCAGAAAGAAAGCGGGUCAUCUGCAGCCUACAGGAACCUAAAACCAGAAGGCAAGUAAGGGAAUUCCUGGGAGCUGUGGGGUUUUGCAGAUUAUGGAUUCCAAACUUUGCUGUACUGGUCAAGUCUUUGUAUGGAGUUACAAAGGGGGGCGACCGGGAGUCUUUUGAAUGGGGACCUCUACAACAGCAAGCCUUUCGUGAGUUAAAGGAAAACCUUAUGUCGGCCCCAGUCCUAGGACUACCAGAUUUGACAAAGCCCUUUACACUGUAUGUGUCAGAAAGAGAUAAAAUGGCAGUUGGAGUUUUAACCCAGACUGUGGGGCCCUGGCCAAGGCCAGUAGCCUAUCUCUCAAAACAACUAGAUGGGGUUUCUAAAGGCUGGGCCCCAUGUCUAAGGGCCCUGGCAGCAACAGCCCUGUUAGCACAAGAAGGAGAUAAACUAACCCUUGGGCAAAACCUGAAUAUAAAGGCCCCCCGUGCUGUGGUAACUUUGAUGAAUACCAAAGGACAGCAUCAGCUAACAAACGCUAGAUUAACCAAGUACCAAAGCUGGCUGUGUGAAAAUUCCCACAUAACCACUGAAGUCUGUAACACCCUAAAUCCCACCACCCUGCUCCCAGUAUGAGAGCCCAGUCGAGCAUAACUGUGUAGAAGUGUUGGACUCAGUUUGUUCUAGCAGACCUGACUUUCAGGACCAGCCAUGGGCAUCAGUAGACUGGGAGUUAUACGUGGAUGGGAGCAGCUUCAUCAACCCACAAGGAGAAAGACAUGCAGGAUAUGUGGUGGUAACUUUGGAUGCUAUCAUUGAAGCCAAACUGUUGCCACAGGGACGUCAGCCCAGAAGGCUGAGCUCACUGCUUUAACUUGGGCUCUAGAACUCAGUGAAGGUAAGACUGUAAACAUCGACACUGACUCUCGAUAUGCCUUUCUAACCCUCCAAGUGCGUGGAGCAUUAUAUAAGGAAAAGGGCCGGUUAAACUCUGGGGGAAAGGACAUAAAAUAUCAACAAGAAAUUCUACAAUUAUUAGAGGCAGUGUGGAAACCUCAGAGAGUGGCAGUCAUGCACUGCAGGGGACACCAGCGAACCUCCACUUCAGUGGCCUUAGGAAACUCCCGAGCUGACUCAGAAGCUCAAAAAGCAGCAUCUACCCCUUACUGGGCAUCGGUAGCAGCCUCCUUACUCCCUCAAACACCUGACCUGGUACCUACCUAUUCUAAGGAAGAAAAAGAAUGUUUCAACACAGAAGGGGGCAAGUAAUAAAAGAAGGAUGGAUCAGACUGCCAGAUGGGAGGGAAGCUGUGCCGCAGUUGCUGGGAGCCACAAUCAUACUGGCCAUGCAUGAAACCACUCAUCUAGGUCAAGAGUCACUUGAAAAGUUGUUAGGCCGGUACUUCUACACUUGCCAGCCCUUGCCAAAGCAGUAGCACAACGGUGCGUUACUUGCAGACAGCAGAACGCAAGGCAAGGCCCCACUGUUCUGCCCGGCCUAUAAGCUUACGGAGUAGCUCCUUUUGAGGAUCUUCAGGUGGAAUUCACAGAAAUGCCAAAAUGUAGAGGUAACAAGUAUUUGCUGGUUCUUGUGUGUACUUACUCUGGGUGGGCGGAGUCUUCCCCAACACGAACCGAAAAGGCCUACGAAGUAACCCUUGUGCUUCUCCGAGACCUUAUUCCUAGGUUUGGACUGCCCUUAUGAAUCAGCUCAGAUAACGGGCCGGCGUUUGUGGCUGACUUGGUACGGAAGACAGCAAAGGCAUUAGGAAUCACUUGGAAGCUGCGUGCCGCCUACUGACCUCAGAGUUUCGGAAAGGUGGAGCGAAUUAAUCGGACUAUCAAAAAUGGUUUAGGGAAAGCACGUCAGGAAACAGGAUUAAAAUGGAUACAGGCCCUUCCUAUGGUAUUGUUUAAAAUUAGAUGCACCCCUUCUAAGAAAACAGGAUACUCCCCUUAUGAAAUACUGUAUCAUAGGCCUCCUACUAUACUACGGGGACUUCCAGGCACUCCCCGAGAGUUAGGUGACAUUGAGUUACAGCGACAGCUACAGGCUUUGGGAAAAAUUACACAGACAAUCUCGACUUGGGUAAAUGAGAGGUGUCCUGUCAGCUUGUUCUCCCCAGUUCAUCCUUUCUUUCCAGUUGAUCGUGUGUGGAUCAAGGACUGGAACGUAGCCCCUUUGCGGCCAUGGUGGAAAGGACCUCAGACCGUCAUCCUGACCACCCCCACGGCUGUAAAGGUAGAAGGAAUCCCAGCCUGGAUCCACCACAGCCAUGUGAAACUGGCAGCCGCUGAAACCUGGGAGGCAAAACCGAGCCCGGACAACCCCUGCGAAGUGACUCUGAGGAGGCCGACAAACCCUGCUCCAGUCACACCCGGAAGCUGACUGGUCUACGCACGGCCGAAGCAUGAGGAGAAUCAUCGUGGGACUCAUUUUCCUUAUAAUUUGGACUUGUAUAGUAAAAACUUCCACUGAUUUUCCCCGCAUGGAGGACUGCUCUCAGUGUAUACAUCAGGUUACUGAGGUAAGGCAACAAGUUAAAACAAUCUUUCUGUUCUAUAGUUACUGUGAAUGCCUAGGAACUUUAAAAGGAACAUGUUUAUAUACUGACACUCAGUACAAGGUAUGUAGCCUAGGAAACGACCGGCCAGCUGUGUGUUAUGACCCCUCUGAGCUUAUCCAACACGAAACUGAAAAGGCCUACGAAGUAACCCGUGUGCUUCCCUGAGACCUUAUUCCUAGGUUUGGACUGCCCUUACGAAUUGGCUUAGAUAAUGGGCCGGCGUUUGUGGCUGACGGUUUUUGAAAUAAGAUUAAGGGCUGAAGACUAGUGGGGACGCGUAAAUGAUACAAGUAAAGUAAUAGCCAGAACAGAAGAGAAAGGGGUGCCCAAACACAUAAUCUUGAAAUUUGAUGCCUGUGCUGUCAUUAGUGGCAGUAAAUUAGGAAAGGGAUGUGGCUCUUUUGGGAAAAAGGCGAUAUGACUGAAAAUAAGUACAUUUGUCAUGAAUUAGGACUGUGUGGAAAUGAAUGUGAACACUGGUCUUGUGUCAUUUAGGCCACUUGGAUAAAAAAAUGAAAAGGAUCCAGUCCACUUCAGAAAGGAAAAAGUGGCCCUUCCUGUACUAAGGGACAAUGUAACCCCUUAGAGCUAGCAACAACCAAUCCCCUUGAUCCUUGCUGGAAAAGAGGGGAGCAUGUGACCUUAGGAAUCGAUGGGGCAGGACUGGAUCCUUGAGUAAAUAUCUUAGUUCGAGGAGAAGUUUACAAACGCUCUGCUCAGCCAGUGUUUCAAACUUUCUAAGAUGAACUAAAUGUGCCAGUACCAGAAAUUCCAGGAAAAACAAGAAAUUUGUUUUUGCAAUUAGCCAAGCAUGUAGCCCAGUCUCUCAGUGUCACUUCAUGUUAUGUAUGUGGAGGAACUGUGAUGGGAGAUCAAUGGCCAUGGGAAGCCCAAGAAUUAGUACCUACAGACCCAGUUCCCAAUGAAUUCCCAGCUCAAAAGAGUCACCUUGAUAAUUUCUGGACCCUGAAGCCUCAAUUAUUGGACAAUAUUGCAUAGCUAGAGAAGGAAAAUAAUUCACUCACCCCUUAGGACAACUUAGUUGUCUGGGACAGAAACUGUAUAAUGGUACCACAAAAACAGUCACUUGGUGGAGUUCAAAUCACACAGAAAGGAAUCCAUUUAGUAAAUUCCCAAGGUUGCAAACCAUGUGGACCCACCUGGAGUCCCACUAGGACUGGACAGCCCCCACUGGAUUAUACUGGCUAUGUGGGCAUAGAGCUUACGCUAAAUUACCUGGCCAGUGGGCAGGUAGUUGUAUUACUGGCACUAUUAAACCAUCUUUCUUCCUACUGUCCAUAAAGACAGGCGAACUCCUGGGCUUCCCUGUCUAUGCUUCCCAUGAAAAAAGAAGCAUAGCUAUAGGAAAUUGGAAAGAUAAUGAAUGGCCCCCAGAGAGAAUCAUACAAUAUUAUGGACCUGCUACUUGGGGACGAGAUGGUUCAUGGGGAUACUAGACCCCCAUUUACAUGCUCAACCAAAUCAUAUGGUUACAAGCUGUCUUAGAAAUAAUCACUAAUAUGGGCUGGGCGCGGUGGCUCACACCUGUAAUCCCAGCACUUUGGGAGGCCAACGCAGGUGGAUCACGAGGUCAGGAGAUUGAGACCAUCCUGGCUAACAUGGUGAAACCCCGUCUCUACUAACAAUACAAAAAAUUAGCCAGGGGUGGUGGCGGGUGCCUGUGGUUCCAGCUACUUGGGAGGCUGAGGCAGGAGAAUGGCGUGAACCUGGGAGGCAGAGCUUGCAGCGAGCCGAGAUUGUGCCACUGCACUCCAGCCUGGGCGACAGAGUGAGACUCCAUCUCAAAAAAAAAAAAAAAAAGAAAAGAAAGAAAGAAUCACUAAUAAAACCGACAGAGCCUUGACUAUUCUGGCCUGUCAAGAGACUCAGAUGAGAAAUGCUAUCUAUCAAAAUAGAUUGGCUCUUGACUACUUGCUAGCAGCUGAAGGAGGGGUCUGUGGGAAAUUUAACCUUACUAAUUGCUGUCUACACGUAGAUGAUCAAGGGCAAGUAGUUGAAGACAUAGUCAGAGAUAUGAUAAAACUGUCACAUGUGCCCAUGCAAGUGUGGCAUGGAUUUGAUCCUGGGGCCAUGUUUGGAAAAUGGUUCCCAGUGUUAGGAGGAUUUAAAACUCUUAUAAUAGGAGUUAUAUUAGUAAUAGGAACCUGCUUACUGCUCCCUUGUUUGCUACCUGUACUUCUUCAAAUGAUAAAAAGCUUCAUCGCUACCUUAGUUCACCAAAAUGCUUCAGAACAACUGUACUAUAUGAAUCACUAUCGAUCUGUCUUGCAAGAAUACAUGGGUAGUGAGGAUGAAAGUGAGAACUCCCACUAAUUGACUGAGGUUCUCAAAGUGGGGGAAUAAGGGAGGAGACCACCCCUCAUAUUGUCUUAUGCCCAAUUUCUGCCUCCAAAGAAAGAAGUAAAAAUUAAAAGGCAGAAAUGGAAUCCACAGGCAGAUAGCCCAGCAUCACGCCCUGGGCCUGGUAGUUAAGAAUCAACCCCUGACCUAACUGCUCGUGUUAUCUAUAGAUUUCAGACAUUGUAUGGAAAAACAUUGUGAAAAUCCCUGUCCUGUUUUAUUCCGUUCUGAUGACCGGUGCAUGCAGCUCCCAGUCACGUACCCACUGCUUGCUUAAUUGAUCACGACCCUCUCACGCGGACCCCGUUAGAGUUGUAAGCCCUUAAAAGGGACAGGAAUUGCUCACUCGGGGAGCUCGGUUUUUGGAAACGUGAGUCUGCUGAUGCUUCCAGCUGAAUAAAGCCCUUUCCUUCCACAA